AGUGUCUCCCGGUCGCGCGUGGAGGUCGGUCGCUCAGAGCUGCUGGGCGCAGUUUCUCCGCCUGCUGCUUCGGCGCGGCUGUAUCGGCGAGCGAGCGAGUUCCCGCGAGUUCUCGGUGGCGCUCCCCCUUCCUUUCAGUCUCCACGGACUGGCCCCUCGUCCUUCUACUUGACCGCUCCCGUCUUCCGCCGCCUUCUGGCGCUUUCCGUUGGGCCGAUUCCCGCCCGCUUCCUCCUGCUUCCCAUCGAAGCUCUAGAAAUGAAUGUUUCCAUCUCUUCAGAGAUGAACCAGGUAAUACGCGCUGGUUCUACGAACGACAGAUGAGGGAGACGGCGCGGCUAGAAUCCGAGAAGAAGGGAUGGCGCCGGCGGAUGGGAAGAGGGUGGGAGGCGCGGAAGCGGUGUCCUCAUCAGGGGAGGCAGCCCCAAGCGGCCGCCGCCGCCCUCUGGGACGUGAAGCCCGCGCCGCGCUGGGCCCGCGCUCCAGCGCUGCCAUGGUUGCCAAGUUGCGUUGGCGGCCGAGAGCGGGCGCCGGUCGCCUCGGAGAGCGCGGAGGCUGGAGCCCCUUUGCUACACUGGCGCGGGUGAGGCAGGCUGGGAGGAACAAGAGUUUUUUGUUCGAAGGGUUUUGGGGGGCCUGGGUUAGGGCGCCGCGGGCGGGGAUGACCCGCCGGAAGGAGGGCGCGGGACUCCCCGUUCUUGCUGUCAGGAACGGACGCCUCGCCUCGGGUUUGCCUGGGGUUUGGGAUUCUCUUCUGGAAGAGCUCUCGAGACUCGGCUCGUGUGGGCGGGCAGCCAGCCCCGGGCCUGGAGUAGGGUGGCACGGAGUCCCCGAUCGCCGUGGGCCGCGGGGUCCUUUGUUCCCGCUCCACGUUGCCCGCUUUUCUUGCCAAGCGCGGGGAGAAGGGGGCGGGAGGAGGGAGGGAGCGGCUGCCCUGACGUGUCGGUACUGAGUGACUGCGGGGCUGGCCAAUCCGGGGCGGGGGUGUGCGGGUGCUGGGGGCCUCGCCUCGCAGCCUGCGGAGUGGGCGCCGGCCUGGCUGCGCGAGGAGGAAGGCCUGGGACGCUCUUUCUUUUUUAUGAAAGAAAUCAGUGGCAAGAUUUGCUCUUUUUCCGUCCCUCCACGCUUUUGGUUAAGUGUCUCUGAUUAUAAGCUCUUGAUGAUAGGAAGGUAUCAGGCUGAGGGUUGAACCUAGGGUAACUUGAACCACUACUUGAGAACUACAUUUACUUUUUCCCCCAAUAGGUAGUGGACAUAUCUAUUGGUUUGAGACAGCUGACAUUUCAAGGAGAAAUCAGAUGUCCAAAAGGGCGCAUUUUUGUGAUGGAGCGUGCAGUGAUGGAGCGUUAGAACACCUUGGCAUCAAGCUGUUCGUUGAGUGUGUCGUGGUCUUCUGUCUACUAAUAGAUGACAACUCUGGAAGCCUAGUACCACUCUUAACAGAUGAAUAAGUACAGCAUGGACUAGACUGCCACAGGCCAUGCUUUCUUUUAAUAAUUCUAGCACCAGUGAUUGAUUUAGGAAAAACAAAAUACUGAUGAUUACUUUUAGGCUAAAGCCUGCUGACACUUCUGUCUUAAAGAUACUGAAAGAGUAGUUGUAUUUGUUAAGUCUGGACGUGAGGUAAACAUGGACUUUAGAAUUGAAUUGAGACUAGUAUCAUUUAACGCCAGCUGGCAGGCUGCUUAUCAAGCUUAUAAUUUGGUAGCCAGAGGUAAACGGAACUUGAGCCACUGACCAAAGAGAGCCCUGGAAUGGUUUUCCUCUGUGUUUUCCUAAUAGAUGAUAUCUCUGGUUAACUAAUAGAUACUAAUUUCUAUAGCCAUUGUCUUAAUUUGUAGUUGAUUUUCUAACUUUCCCCCCAAGACAAAACAUUUCAGGUUUUAGUCUUAGUUUUAAAUUAGUGUCUUUUUGGCUACUUGCUUUUGGAAGGUGGGAUUUUUUCUUGCUUGAAGGAUUUGUUAGAUGGUAAUUAAAUGUAGUUUUGCAAAUACGUUUUUAAAUAUAAAUGUUUUCCUGUUAAGGAAGUAUCUUAAUUGAUAUUAAGAUGAAGUAACACUAAGUAAGUCAUUUCAUCCACUUUUUAGCAGUGCGAUUGUAUAGUCAAAUCCUGCAAGUAGGAAUUAUUAAAGGUUGGGGGUCUUCCCACCAUGUCAUGUGCAUGUGCUAGUGUGUGUGUAGAUUGAAGUAUUGUGAGUAAGAGAUUGAUUUCUGGGUUUUUGUUAAAACAACAGAAAAUACAUACUUGUAAACUACAAGUUGUAUAUCUUGUAAAUGUUUCUGAACCUAUACUUAACAUCAUACUAUUAUAUUUUUGUUAUUAACAUGCAGAUACCUCAGCAUUAGAACGUCUCAAACCAAAUUCUUCCUUUCCUUCCUUCCCUUCUCCAUGUAGCAAACUAUAAACGACUUUGUGUUAUGCUUUUUGGUAAUUGAUUUUAAUAAGGAUGCCACAUAUCUUAAUUUUGAUAAUUGAUGUUAAUAAGGAUGCCACAUAUCUAAGAUAAAAUAUCUUAAGUCCUCACUGCCUUAAAGGAGCAUGGGUGUACAGAAUCUUAACUGCCCUGUUUCCAUGCUUUACUCAUUCCUCUAGACCAUCCCCCACACUUCUGCUAGGAUGCCCUAUGCUUCCUUGUUUAAAUCCUUCACCUACUUUCCAUGCUUAGCAUUGUUUAAACCUUGGAAUUAGGCUCUCUUACUUCCUCGCCCACUAUUACCAUAUGCAUCCUGCAAAUCUACAAUCUAUUGAAACUGAAAUAGCUGCAGUUUCUGGAAUAUAUUUGCUAUCAUACCUUUUUUCCUUUCUGCUUAAGCUAUUUCACAGCUUGUUUUAUCUUUCUGACUGGCCUGUGAAGUGUUCCAGGCUAGAGAACUGAGUUAACUUCUAUUGUGUUAUGAUAUGAGCAUUCCAUUUCAGUUUGUGCCUUCCAUAUGUUUGGUGCUACAUAUGUUUGUGUUGUAGUGAAAGAAUUACAAAACUAUGAGCAUGGAUAGAAUGAAUGAGUUCAGCGAGUUUUCAUAUACAUGGAUGGUGAUGGUGGUUUUAGAGGUUACUUUGGAAAGCUGUAACUUCUGGUUUUAAAAAGAUGUGUUGAUUUACUUUGUAUUAUAAAGUCUUUCCUUUAAAAAUGCAGCUGAUGGCUACUUGGUGGGAGCUGACUGCCCUCAAACGAUUGUCUUUUGUUUUAUCUUGGUCUUACUGAAGGCCAGAGAAAAAUUUUAGCAGAGGCCAUAUUGUGCCUACCUUUUUAACAACUCUUUGAUAAGACCUGUUGAAUUGUAUUUCACUUAAGCUAAUCUUUCCGGGCUGUGAACUUCUGGGUGUUAUUAAAGCAGUUUAAUUACUCAUUUAUGAGUCUUCGGUAUCCCUUGCAGUGGCCAUAGAAGUAUGCUGAAUUUAUCUGAAUAUAUUGUAUUUGAUCCUAGUUUUAAUUUUAAAUGUGUAAGAAAAGUGACCUAGGUGUAGAUUUAGUUGAAAGUGUAUUUUAAACACCAAACAAUUCUACGUUUCAUACUCUUAUAUGACUCUGGGAUGUCUGGACUUUUGGUUUGGAUUUUCAAAGAAAACAAUUUUCCCCAUUUUUUAAUUCCACUAGUUAUCGUGCUUGAGUUUUAUAGACCAAAUAAGAUCUCCCGUCAAUUUGGGGAGUAGUUUAAAACUCUUGAUUUGCCCUAGCUCACUUUAAUGAAAGUAAAUAGGAACUUUCAAAAACAUGGUUUUACAGACAGGAAUUGAUCUGAUCCCCUCCAAACUUGAGGUGGGCGGGAAGUAGGUAUAUAGUGUAUGAGGACAAUAAUUGAAUAAAGUAAGUUUGCAUUAACUUAAAUGUCAUCUAGAUUUGGGCUGGCUUUUAAAAUCAAGUAGCUUUGUACUCUGAUCAGUAGAUAUUAAAGAGAUGAGGUUCAUAUUAUGACCUUGAUGUACUAAAAAUCAGGUACUGUCAUGGAAUUAGAGUAAAAACUAAAUAAAAAUCAAGCACUAAAUACAGGAUUCAUUUUACUGCAAAACUCAUAAUAAUAUUGUACAAAUUUGUCUGAUGCAAAUUGCCCCAAAAAUUCUCCAGUGUUUUCUCCAAGGGCUGCAGUAAUUUUAACCAUUUUUUUCCAAAAUAAAUUUUAGGUAGAUCAUUCAAUUUGUCAAAUAUAGUAAGUGGAUACCAUUUUUAUUUUUUGUUAGAUCAAGUUUACAAGUAAAAAGUGAGUAAAACUGGUCAAAGUUUAAAAUAGUACCUUCAUAUUAUAAUGUUUUUGGCUUUUCAGAGGAUGCAUUUUAAUAUAACAAUUUGCAUGGGGACUCCUUCCUCUUAUUUUAAGAGCAGCUUAUGAAACUGAAGUUAGGAGUUGCCAACUAUGCCUGUGAAUUGACCAUGCCAGUAUAAAUCAUAUAUAUAUGAAAAUUUUCUUAGUUUGAGCCAGGUCUUGGCUGAAAAUGUUUGAAGGUUUCUUUAGGAUAGUGUGUUCUCUCUGUGUAGAAAGAAUUAUGUAUAUUUGGAAAACAUUUGUUAGAACUAGUUUCUUAGAGAAAAGCCAAAUUAACUAACCUAGAUAAAAGGUAGAGCAGAGGAAAUCAAUAUUACCUAAUGCUGUGAUAUAGUUUUGAUGCAAGGGUAAGCAUUCACAACAAUCCCAACCCGAAUUGGCAUUAUUGGGUUUCCUUGAAAUGAAACCUGUUACAGAGAGACCUGUUAGGACACAUGUUGAACUAAACAUAGUAGGUUUGUUGAAUUCGAACUGGACCAGCCUGCAGUGGAGUCCUGUGAUUAUGAUGCAUCAUUAUCACAGAAGAAAUUCGUGUCUAUAGCUUUUAAGGACUUGAUUACAUCAUUUUCAAGCCUGAUAGUUUUGGAAUCACCAUUAGAGCUUAAGACACACCUGCCUUCAUUUCAACCACCUGUCUUCAUACCCUGACGAAGUGCACCUUUUAACACUCCUUUGUCCUUGGAUUACUUAAGAGUUCCCAGAAAUACAUUUGCCACCAACAGAGUAGCCAAAUUUAUAAGGAAAAAUGAUUCCCAAUGGAUAUUUGAUGUUUGAGGAUGAAAAUUUUAUUGAGUCUUCUGUUGCCAAAUUAAAUGCCCUGAGGAAAAGUGGCCAGUUCUGUGAUGUUCGACUUCAGGUCUGUGGCCAUGAAAUGUUAGCACACAGAGCAGUGCUAGCUUGCUGCAGUCCCUAUUUAUUUGAAAUCUUUAAUAGUGAUAGUGAUCCUCAUGGAAUUUCUCACGUUAAAUUUGAUGAUCUCAAUCCAGAAGCUGUUGAAGUCUUGUUGAAUUAUGCCUACACUGCUCAGUUGAAAGCAGAUAAGGAAUUGGUAAAAGAUGUUUAUUCUGCAGCAAAAAAGCUGAAGAUGGAUCGAGUAAAGCAGGUUUGUGGUGAUUAUUUACUGUCUAGAAUGGAUGUUACCAGCUGCAUCUCUUACCGAAAUUUUGCAAGUUGUAUGGGAGACUCCCGUUUGUUGAAUAAGGUUGAUGCUUAUAUUCAGGAGCAUUUGUUACAAAUUUCUGAAGAGGAGGAGUUUCUUAAGCUUCCAAGGCUAAAGUUGGAGGUAAUGCUUGAAGAUAAUGUUUGCUUGCCCAGCAAUGGCAAAUUAUAUACAAAGGUAAUCAACUGGGUGCAGCGUAGCAUCUGGGAGAAUGGAGACAGUCUGGAAGAGCUGAUGGAAGAGGUUCAAACCUUGUACUACUCAGCUGAUCACAAGCUGCUUGAUGGGAACCUACUAGAUGGACAGGCUGAGGUGUUUGGCAGUGAUGAUGACCACAUUCAGUUUGUGCAGAAAAAGCCACCACGUGAGAAUGGCCAUAAGCAGAUAAGUAGCAGUUCAACUGGAUGUCUCUCUUCUCCAAAUGCUACAGUACAAAGCCCUAAGCAUGAGUGGAAAAUCGUUGCUUCAGAAAAGACUUCAAAUAACACUUACUUGUGCCUGGCUGUGCUGGAUGGUAUAUUCUGUGUCAUUUUUCUUCAUGGGAGAAACAGCCCACAGAGCUCACCAACAAGUACUCCAAAACUAAGUAAGAGUUUAAGCUUUGAGAUGCAACAAGAUGAGCUAAUCGAAAAGCCCAUGUCUCCUAUGCAGUACGCACGAUCUGGUCUGGGAACAGCAGAGAUGAAUGGCAAACUCAUAGCUGCAGGUGGCUAUAACAGAGAGGAAUGUCUUCGAACAGUCGAAUGCUAUAAUCCACAUACAGAUCACUGGUCCUUUCUUGCUCCCAUGAGAACACCAAGAGCCCGAUUUCAAAUGGCUGUACUCAUGGGCCAGCUCUAUGUGGUAGGUGGAUCAAAUGGCCACUCAGAUGACCUGAGUUGUGGAGAGAUGUAUGAUUCAAACAUAGAUGACUGGAUUCCUGUUCCAGAAUUGAGAACUAACCGUUGUAAUGCAGGAGUGUGUGCUCUGAAUGGAAAGUUAUACAUCGUUGGUGGCUCUGAUCCAUAUGGUCAAAAAGGACUGAAAAAUUGUGAUGUAUUUGAUCCUGUAACAAAGUUGUGGACAAGCUGUGCCCCUCUUAACAUUCGGAGACACCAGUCUGCAGUCUGUGAGCUUGGUGGUUAUUUGUACAUAAUCGGAGGUGCAGAAUCUUGGAAUUGUCUGAACACAGUAGAACGAUACAAUCCUGAAAAUAAUACCUGGACUUUAAUUGCACCCAUGAAUGUGGCUAGGCGAGGAGCUGGAGUGGCUGUUCUUAAUGGAAAACUGUUUGUAUGUGGUGGCUUUGAUGGUUCUCAUGCCAUCAGUUGUGUGGAAAUGUAUGAUCCAACUAGAAAUGAAUGGAAGAUGAUGGGAAAUAUGACUUCACCAAGGAGCAAUGCUGGGAUUGCAACUGUAGGGAACACCAUUUAUGCAGUGGGAGGAUUCGAUGGCAAUGAAUUUCUGAAUACGGUGGAAGUCUAUAACCUUGAGUCAAAUGAAUGGAGCCCCUAUACAAAGAUUUUCCAGUUUUAACAAAUUUAAGACCCUCUCAAACUAACAGGCUUAGUGAUGUAAUUAUGGUUAGUAGAGGUACACUUGUGAAUAAAGAGGGUGGGUGGGUAUAGAUGUUGCUAACAGCAACACAAAGCUUUUGCAUAUUGCAUACUAUUAAACAUGCUGUACAUACUUUUUGGGUUUAUUUGGAAAGGAAUGCAAAGAUGAAGGUCUGUUUUGUGUACUUUUAAGACUUUGGUUAUUUUACUUUUUGGAAAAGAAUAAACCAAGAAUUGAUUGGGCACAUCAUUUCAAGAAGUCCCCUCUCCUCCACAUUUGUUUUGCCAAUUUGCACAUUAAAUGACUCUUCCCUCAAAUGUGUACUAUGGGGUAAAAGGGGUAGGGUUUAAAGAUGUAGACAGUUGGGUUUUUUAAGGGCCCUUUUUCAAUAACUGGAACACUCUAUAACAAAGGAUACUUAUUUAAAUAGAUGACAUUGACUAUUUUUGUUUUUAUUAAAAGGAAGCUUACAUGCCUACCAAUAUUUAAUCUUUUAUGAUUGCCUUUUUAUAACUUUUUAUAUUCUCAGCAGAGUGCUUUACCAAUUGAAGUAAAAUGUGGCAGGCUGGAGUUAUUGAAGCAGAGUGGCAGUCUUCAGUUUGCAGAGUAGGGGUCUGUCUUUUAAACUCUGAGUGCAAACUUCAGAGUUCUUGCCUUGGCUGCAGUUUUUUUCCUUCAAGAAUGCAGUACUAACAUUUAUUUGAGUGGAGUUACUGAACAGUAACAUAGCUGUGAUUUUUGGUAUUUGAAACACUGGUUUUAAAUAUUUUGACUUGUUGAGGGUAUGUUUUAUAUAGCAAGACAUUAUAUAGCAGUAAAAAAUGGUGUUUUAUCUUCUAUAUAAUUCCUGUUUUUAUUAUUAACAAAACAGUCCUAAAUAGCAGCCCUCAAUUGUGAAAAAAUUUACUUUAAACUACAUUAGGUUGUGAAUGCAGGUUUUAUCAGAACUAUGUUUUUGUUCAGUUUAUCUGUUCAUAUGGAUAAAUAUUGGUUGGGAUGACUUGGUGUCUAAUGUGUAGUGCUACACACCUAACUUAUGGGGCCAAAAUAGCAUGUCCUAAUGCUUGCUGCUGAUUUAAACACAUUAAAGGUACUUUGCAGGAAAUCCUUGCACCAUGGGAUUAAUAUCCAAUUGCUGCUUGUACACUCAUUCAUUACUAAAAGUUUUGAGAAAUUUUUUUUUCCAGUAAUGAGCUUAAGAAAUUUGUGGAAAAUAACUCACCUGGCAUCUUACAUCUGAAAUAAGGAAUGAUAUAAGGUUUUUUUUUCUCACAGAAGAUGAAGCACACAGGAACCUAAUGGGCCAACUGGGAUGAGGUGACUAUUCUGAGAUGACUAUUCAGUGGCUAACUUGGGUUAGGAAGAAAAUAAUUAGGUAUUUUCUCCAAAUGUUCACUGGUACUCUGCCACUUUAUUUCUCUCAUCUGUUACACAAAGAACCACCAGGAAAGCAAAUCAGUUUGGUUGGUAACUCUGUAAUUCCUAACUAUCACUGGUUUGGUUCUGGACUAAAACUACAUUGACAGAUUGAAUUUGCCUAAUAUGAUGACUGUUUUUAAUAUGGAUCUGUAUGUGUUCUAUUCAGCACAAGGAAAUAAAAUUUUAGUUGAGGAUUCAGCACUAAAA